GUUGUUGUUGGUGGCGGCGGCGAGCGGAGCCGGAGGAGCCGCCGCAAAGAUGGAGGAGCCGUCGAGGAGGUGCUGCCGCCGCUGCCGCCGCCGCUGCUGCCGCCGCCGCCCGCGAAGCCGGAGCUCGAGCCGCAGCGGGUGAGCGCGCCGCCCCGGCCCAGAUCCCAUCUUCCCCGGACCCCGGGACGCGAGGCGGCGCCCCCUCCUCCUGCUGUCUCUGUCCGCGGGCUCCCAGCGCGCGCGCCGCGCUCCGCGCCCCCCUUCCUUCCUCCCGGCCCUGGGAGCCAGCCGGCGCCCCCCGGGAGCAUCGGCAGCCCGUGAGCGGGACAUCGGGGUUGCUGCGCGCGCCCCUCCCUGCCCCUCCCAGACAGGGGCGCCUUCCCUACAGGGAUGCCGUUCUGAGUGCCUGACUGCCUCGCCCCGAAGGAUGGCCUCGGAUGGGCAUUAGAGGCACGGCGGCCCCGGGCUCCCGUCCCGUCCGUCUGUCUGUUAUCGUCUGUCUCUCUUGACAUCACCGCAGCUCCACCCCCUCCCGUCCCAGCCCCCAACGCCAGCUUCCUGCAGGCCCAGAGCCGGCAUGAACUCUCCCAACGAGUCGGCAGAUGGGAUGUCAGGUCGGGAACCAUCCUUGGAAAUCCUGCCGCGGACUUCUCUGCACAGCAUCCCUGUGACAGUGGAGGUGAAGCCGGUGCUGCCAAGAGCCAUGCCCAGUUCCAUGGGGGGUGGGGGUGGAGGCAGCCCCAGCCCUGUGGAGCUACGGGGGGCUCUGGUGGGCUCUGUGGACCCCACACUGCGGGAGCAGCAACUGCAGCAGGAGCUCCUGGCGCUCAAGCAGCAGCAGCAGCUGCAGAAGCAGCUCCUGUUCGCUGAGUUCCAGAAACAGCAUGACCACCUGACAAGGCAGCAUGAGGUCCAGCUGCAGAAGCACCUCAAGCAGCAGCAGGAGAUGCUGGCAGCCAAGCAGCAGCAGGAGAUGCUGGCAGCCAAGCGGCAGCAGGAGCUGGAGCAGCAGCGGCAGCGGGAGCAGCAGCGGCAGGAAGAGCUGGAGAAGCAGCGGCUGGAGCAGCAGCUGCUCAUCCUGCGGAACAAGGAGAAGAGCAAAGAGAGUGCCAUUGCCAGCACUGAGGUAAAGCUGAGGCUCCAGGAAUUCCUCUUGUCGAAGUCAAAGGAGCCCACACCAGGCGGCCUCAACCAUUCCCUCCCACAGCACCCCAAAUGCUGGGGAGCCCACCAUGCUUCUUUGGACCAGAGUUCCCCUCCCCAGAGCGGCCCCCCUGGGACGCCUCCCUCCUACAAACUGCCUUUGCCUGGGCCCUACGACAGUCGAGACGACUUCCCCCUCCGCAAAACAGCCUCUGAACCCAACUUGAAAGUGCGUUCAAGGCUAAAACAGAAGGUGGCUGAGCGGAGAAGCAGUCCCCUCCUGCGUCGCAAGGAUGGGACUGUUAUUAGCACCUUUAAGAAGAGAGCUGUUGAGAUCACAGGUGCCGGGCCUGGGGCGUCGUCCGUGUGUAACAGCGCACCCGGCUCCGGCCCCAGCUCUCCCAACAGCUCCCACAGCACCAUCGCUGAGAAUGGCUUUACUGGCUCAGUCCCCAACAUCCCCACUGAGAUGCUCCCUCAGCACCGAGCCCUCCCUCUGGACAGCUCCCCCAACCAGUUCAGCCUCUACACGUCUCCUUCUCUGCCCAACAUCUCCCUAGGGCUGCAGGCCACGGUCACUGUCACCAACUCACACCUCACUGCCUCCCCGAAGCUGUCGACACAGCAGGAGGCCGAGAGGCAGGCCCUCCAGUCCCUGCGGCAGGGUGGCACGCUGACCGGCAAGUUCAUGAGCACAUCCUCUAUUCCUGGCUGCCUGCUGGGCGUGGCACUGGAGGGCGACGGGAGCCCCCACGGGCAUGCCUCCCUGCUGCAGCAUGUGCUGUUGCUGGAGCAGGCCCGGCAGCAGAGCACCCUCAUUGCUGUGCCACUCCACGGGCAGUCCCCACUAGUGACGGGUGAACGUGUGGCCACCAGCAUGCGGACGGUAGGCAAGCUCCCGCGGCAUCGGCCCCUGAGCCGCACUCAGUCCUCACCGCUGCCGCAGAGUCCCCAGGCCCUGCAGCAGCUGGUCAUGCAACAACAGCACCAGCAGUUCCUGGAGAAGCAGAAGCAGCAGCAGCUACAGCUGGGCAAGAUCCUCACCAAGACAGGGGAGCUGCCCAGGCAGCCCACCACCCACCCUGAGGAGACAGAGGAGGAGCUGACGGAGCAGCAGGAGGUCUUGCUGGGGGAGGGAGCCCUGACCAUGCCCCGGGAGGGCUCCACAGAGAGUGAGAGCACACAGGAAGACCUGGAGGAGGAGGACGAGGAAGACGAUGGGGAGGAGGAGGAGGAUUGCAUCCAGGUUAAGGACGAGGAGGGCGAGAGUGGUGCUGAGGAGGGGCCCGACUUGGAGGAGCCUGGUGCUGGAUACAAAAAACUGUUCUCAGAUGCCCAGCCGCUGCAGCCUUUGCAGGUGUACCAGGCGCCCCUCAGCCUGGCCACUGUGCCCCACCAGGCCCUGGGCCGUACCCAGUCCUCCCCUGCUGCCCCUGGGGGCAUGAAGAGCCCCCCAGACCAGCCCGUCAAGCACCUCUUCACCACAGGUGUGGUCUACGACACGUUCAUGCUAAAGCACCAGUGCAUGUGCGGGAACACACACGUGCACCCUGAGCAUGCUGGCCGGAUCCAGAGCAUCUGGUCCCGGCUGCAGGAGACAGGCCUGCUUAGCAAGUGCGAGCGGAUCCGAGGUCGCAAAGCCACGCUAGAUGAGAUCCAGACAGUGCACUCUGAAUACCACACCCUGCUCUAUGGGACCAGUCCCCUCAACCGGCAGAAGCUAGACAGCAAGAAGUUGCUCGGCCCCAUCAGCCAGAAGAUGUAUGCUGUGCUGCCUUGUGGGGGCAUCGGGGUGGACAGUGACACCGUGUGGAAUGAGAUGCACUCCUCCAGUGCUGUGCGCAUGGCAGUGGGCUGCCUGCUGGAGCUGGCCUUCAAGGUGGCUGCAGGAGAGCUCAAGAAUGGAUUUGCCAUCAUCCGGCCCCCAGGACACCACGCCGAGGAAUCCACAGCCAUGGGAUUCUGCUUCUUCAACUCUGUAGCCAUCACCGCAAAACUCCUACAGCAGAAGUUGAACGUGGGCAAGGUCCUCAUCGUGGACUGGGACAUUCACCAUGGCAAUGGCACCCAGCAGGCGUUCUACAAUGACCCCUCUGUGCUCUACAUCUCUCUGCAUCGCUAUGACAACGGGAACUUCUUUCCAGGCUCUGGGGCUCCUGAAGAGGUUGGUGGAGGACCAGGCGUGGGGUACAAUGUGAACGUGGCAUGGACAGGAGGUGUGGACCCCCCCAUUGGAGACGUGGAGUACCUUACAGCCUUCAGGACAGUGGUGAUGCCCAUUGCCCACGAGUUCUCACCUGAUGUGGUCCUAGUCUCCGCCGGGUUUGAUGCUGUUGAAGGACAUCUGUCUCCUCUGGGUGGCUACUCUGUCACCGCCAGAUGUUUUGGCCACUUGACCAGGCAGCUGAUGACCCUGGCAGGGGGCCGGGUGGUGCUGGCCCUGGAGGGAGGCCAUGACUUGACCGCCAUCUGUGAUGCCUCUGAGGCUUGUGUCUCGGCUCUGCUCAGUGUAGAGCUGCAGCCCUUGGAUGAGGCAGUCUUGCAGCAAAAGCCCAACAUCAACGCAGUGGCCACGCUAGAGAAAGUCAUCGAGAUCCAGAGCAAACACUGGAGCUGUGUGCAGAAGUUCGCCGCUGGUCUGGGCCGGUCCCUGCGAGAGGCCCAAGCAGGUGAGACCGAGGAGGCCGAGACUGUGAGCGCCAUGGCCUUGCUGUCGGUGGGGGCCGAGCAGGCCCAGGCUGCGGCAGCCCGGGAACACAGCCCCAGGCCGGCAGAGGAGCCCAUGGAGCAGGAGCCUGCCCUGUGACGCCCCGGCCCCCAUCCCUCUGGGCUUCACCAUUGUGAUUUUGUUUAUUUUUUCUAUUAAAAACAAAAAGUCACACAUUCAACAAGGUGUGCCGUGUGGGUCUCUCAGCCUUGCCCCUCCUGCUCCUCUACGCUGCCUCAGGCCCCCAGCCCUGUGGCUUCCACCUCAGCUCUAGAAGCCUGCUCCCUCUGCAGGGGGUGGUGGUGUCUUCCCAGCCCUGUCCCAUGUGUCCCUCCCCCCAUUUUCCUGCAUUCUGUCUGUCCUUUUCCUCCUUGGAGCCUGGGCCAGCUCAAGGUGGGCACGGGGGCCCAGACAGUACUCUCCAGUUCUGGGGCCCCCCGAGUGAGGAGGGAACGGGAAGUCGGUGCCUUGGUUUCAGCUGAUUUGGGGGGAAAUGCCUUAAUUUCACUCUCCUCCCUUCUCCAGCCUCAGGGGAGGAUCUGGAGGAUCCACUACUGUCUUUAAGAUGCAGAGUGGAGGGGAGGUGGGCACCCACCCUGCGAUUCUCCACCCUUUCCCCUUCUUUCGUCCUCACCAUCUCUGCAGACCCCUCUCCUCCUCCUUCCUCUUGGUCUCAGCACUGAUGGGAGGCUGGUGCCCAAGCUGUGGCCUGCAGUCUGUGAGGAGGGCUGUCUUGCCUCACACUCCUCACAGCCUACUUCCCCUUCCCCGGGGCUGAGAGGGUGAAAGUGUGUGGGGAAGGAGAGGACUGGUUUCCUGGGUUCUCAGGGGCCAGGAGGAGUAACAGAACCAGGUCUGCUCCCCACCUUACUCGGAUGGCCUCCCUGCCCCUCUGCUGGCACAGCCUGGGCAAGGGGAGAAGGUGGUCCCUGCAGAGGGGCUCCAGGCUGGUGAGAGCCCCCCUGCUGUCAGGACCAGAUUUUCCCAGCCAUCCAGCAUGCUGCGGGGAGAAGGGGCAGAGGCUCACCUCCCUCCUGGGGCCUUUUGUUUUGGAUCCUGGGGAUGGUGAGAAUGGAGGUUCUAGAAGGGGUAAGGCCAGAACCCAGGGAUCCAGGAGUCGGCUCUCAGCUGGAGCUUCCAUACCUUCUGGGCUCCCUUUGCUGACCACCAGCCCAAGGGAGCUAAGACCAGGAGGGGGCUGGGCGCUGUCCCUUCUCUUUCCCAGGAGCCCUGCCAGGGGCUGUGGGCCUACAAGGCUUCCAGGGGAUGCCAUCCAGCCUGUAGGAAACCAAAGAUGGGAAGUGGCUCCUAGGGGGCUGACUCUUCCUUCCUCCUCCUCCCCAGUACCACAUAUACUUUCUCUCCUUCUAUCUCCAGGGCCCCACCAAUCUGUUUACAUAUUUAUUAUCCUAUGGGGGCCUGAGCAGGAUUGAGGGAGCCAGGGGAGGGGCAGGAGUCCCAGCACCAUCGGUUCAUAGUGUGCUUGUGUGUUUGUUUUAGAUCCUCCUGGGGGAUGGGGAUGGGGCCAGGCUCAGUGUACUAGGCCUCUCUGUGCUGAGCCCCAGGCUCCCGGCCCCUUACCCACUCUCUCCCUGUGGCUGGUCUGGUUCUCAUGUAAACCCACUCCUUGCUUUGUCUCCCUGGAUAUGGAUUUCAGUUAAGUAUUUUGUAACCCGUUACACUGUGUGUCCUUGUGUAAAUAAACUUGUUUCUGGCAGUGCC